CCUGCCUGAGUUCGCCAGUGGUCCAGGAGCCGCUUUUUUCCACUCGGGAAGACUUCAGAGAAGUCUCACAAAGGACUCGGCUGGCUGCUUUUCUCAGUGCCGAAGCCGCGCCAUGCUCGUUCUCAGAAGCGGCCUGACCAAGGCGCUUGCCUCACGGACGCUCGCGCCUCAGGUGUGUUCAUCUUUUGCUACGGGCCCUAGACAAUACGAUGGAACGUUCUAUGAAUUUCGUACUUAUUACCUUAAACCUUCAAAUAUGAAUGCGUUCAUGGAAAAUCUUAAGAAAAACAUUCAUCUUCGGACCUCUUACUCUGAAUUGGUUGGAUUCUGGAGUGUAGAAUUUGGAGGCAGAACGAAUAAAGUGUUUCAUAUUUGGAAGUAUGAUAAUUUUGCUCAUCGAGCUGAAGUUCGGAAAGCCUUAGCCAACUGUAAGGAAUGGCAAGAACAAUCUAUCAUUCCAAAUUUGGCUCGCAUUGAUAAACAAGAGACGGAAAUUACUUACCUGAUACCAUGGUCCAAAUUAGAAAAGCCUCCAAAAGAAGGAGUCUAUGAACUAGCUGUUUUUCAGAUGAAACCUGGUGGGCCAGCUCUGUGGGGUGAUGCAUUUGAAAGAGCAAUUAAUGCCCAUGUCAAUUUAGGCUACACAAAAGUAGUUGGUGUUUUCCACACAGAAUAUGGAGAACUCAACAGAGUUCAUGUUCUUUGGUGGAAUGAGAGUGCAGAUAGUCGUGCAGCUGGGAGACAUAAGUCCCAUGAGGAUCCCAGAGUUGUGGCGGCUGUUCGGGAAAGUGUCAACUACCUAGUUUCUCAGCAGAAUAUGCUUCUGAUUCCUGCAUCAUUUUCACCAUUGAAAUAGUUUUCUACUGAAAUACAAAACAUUUCAUUAACUGCUCUAAGAUGUGUCUGCUAAUGGUGCUUAAAUUCUCCCAAGAGGUUCUCGCUUUUAUUUGAAGGAGGUGGUAAGUUAAUUAGUUAAUUUGCUGUGCUUCUUGCAUUUUUGAAAGUUACAUAUUCUCCACUGCUUUAAGAAAUAAUUCAGUUCACUUUCACCUUGGCAUUUCAGUAUCUGUUACACAUUAGAAGUAGUUGUCACUAUUUCAUCAUCUUGGUUUUUCAUUUGUUUUAGAAUACCUCUUCUGUAUUUUGAUAACUCAUUGCUUUAUAGCAUUUUCUUUUACUCAAAUAAGGAUUUUACAUUUCCUUGCCUGACAGUAUUUUUGAAUUAUUUAUAUAAAAUAUCUAUCUUUUCAUCAUGUCUAUAGUUCCUGAGAUUUUAAAAAAAUUUGCUUAGUAAAGGUUAUUUUGUGAUAUAAAAUGGGAUUUAUAAAAAUAUUAGAUUGUUUAUUUCUUUACUGUGGAAAAGUACAAUGUCAUCUGUAUUAAUUAUUGCUUUUACAUUCAUUGAUUAUUAGUCAUUCUAACUUGGAAAAUAAUGCAAUUGGGUCACAGUGUUAAAAAUCUAGAAAAGACUUGUUGGUUUAUAUGCUGAAAUUGUUCAUUUAUAAUUAAUUUUACUAAUUUCUACUUAGUUUGGAUCACUAACAGAGAUCUUGGGACAUUUAUUUGUUUUAAAGAAAUAUUUAUGGUUAUGGAAACGCUUGCCCUAAUAAAAAUCCUGCAUAUUCAUUGUUUUUUUAAAUUCACAUUUUAUACUUAUAUGAUCUCUAAAGCUCUUGCUAUGUUGCUAUAAGACAGUAAUAUAGUGAUAAUUUACCAACUUUAUUGAAAAUGUUGUUACAUCAAUAAAAUAGCAUGCUGGGAACCUGAGAAGGAAGGUUUCUUUAGUACUGCCACAGAUGUCCUGGAGUUUUCCUUGAAACAUCUUUCAUUUCCAUUUUACUUGAUGCCUCUACCUACUAAAACUAGAUUUGGUACUUCCGAUAGUGUAUAUUUACAGCUAUAUUAUAUUUACAUUUUUACAGACUAUCUUCUGAUAAUCUGUAUUUACAGCUAUGUUAUUUUAUAUUUUUAAAAUCUUACAGCUAUAAAAUAGUAAAUUGUGAAUUAGCUGUCCAAGGGCAAUUUGGAAAACAAACUGUACAGUUUCCUCUCAUUUAUCAGGCUCUAAGCGAUCUGCAGUUUAUCUGGGCUAUUAUGCAAUGUGAGAUAUUAUUUAUGAGAGGCAGGCAGUGGCAGCUUAAACAGACAUACCUCCUCAGCAUUCUUUUCCAUGCAGAGUUCAAAGAGGCCUAAGACAUCUCACAUUUAUGUGAAAUAGUUGAGGCACAAGUAUGUGGUUAACUACACAUAAAUUACCAAUAAAAUUAAAAGUUAACUAAAAUACUACAGAAGACAUUUAAUAUUUUGCUUCAGACUGUUAUAGUACCUUAGGGUUAUGAACAUCAAUUACCUUUGAGCCUUACUAUAUUUAAAGGGAAGGGGAAGCUGACAUUUUUAUCUUUUUUAAUGGGUACACUCUACGUUACCUUAAAGGCUUCCCCGGUUUAAGCAAAAAUAGAAUUAUGUGGUUUAAAUCAUAUACCUUAUUCUUCAUACUUAGCUCCAAGUAGAUUAUGACUUUUCCUAAAACUUAACAUGACAGAGAUUUGCCUUCCAGGGGGUCUAAUUUGAAGAGGAAAGUAAUUUAAAUGUAUAGGUUUAUAUAAUAGCAUUGUAUUUUUCUCUAUUUUAUUCAUUCUUUCAUUCUCUUCGAUGACUCCCAGCACCUGCGCGUCCAUCUUCAUUCUUAGCCAAUGACCUUUCCUUUUACUUAACAGAGAAAAUAACAAUCAGAAGAGUCUUCAUAAGUUCCCACCCCGUCUGCCCGCUUUCUACAGCCAACCCCACAUGCCCUGCCUUCUCUCCUUUCACUGUGGAUGAACCGCCCGUGCCCCAAGCAAAGACAAACCCUCCACUUGAACACUCACUUGCUGAAGGAUGUGGCUUAGGCAGUUUUCCUGUCUCCUGAAGCCACAGUAUUCCCCUUCAACUGGAUUCUUCUCCUCAGCAUAUAAAUAUACUUUUUUUUCCUAUCUUUAAAAAAAAAAAAGAGUAAAAUCACCCCAUUUUUUUCCUUUACAAUAUGACUCAAAAGAGUAGUUCAUACUUCCUGCCUCCAUUUUCUUCCCUCACAUUAUCUCUUAAACAUUCUCUGAUCACGCCAGCCAAAUUGCUCUUGUCAACUCAUUUCCCAGUUCUCAUUUCACUUGACUUGUUAGCAGUUGACCUCUCCUUUCUUCUGGGAAGUUUCUUCGUUUCUCCGAAACACUCACUGCACAAGCCUUCAUAUCUCCUAGUCUCCAUCUUGUCUCUUUGACCUCUGAUGUAAGGACUGAGUCCUUGGACCACUUCUCUUUUCUAUUUAUACUUACUCCCUGCGUCAUCACCCCCAGUCUUGUGGCUUCAAAUGCUAUCUGUGUGUGGAUAGCUCCUCCAGUCCACACCUCUUUUCUGAAUCUUUUUUCAAAUUCACACAUGUGAAUUUGAAUUCCAGGCUCAUCACAUCCAGGUGUGUUCCCCACACCUCCACCUGAAUGUCUAUUAGAAAUCUCACACCCCUCUUGUCCAAAACUGAGCUCUUGAUCUUUAACCAGAAACUUUAUCUCAGCUAUUGGCAACUCCAGGUUUCUGUUUUGCUCAGGCCACAGACUUCAGAGUCAUUCUCACACUGCCUUUUCUCUCAUACACCAUUAUGUACCUGUCAGCAGGUCCCAAAUAUCUAGAAUUUGAUUGCUUCACAUCCCUAUAGCAACUCUCCUGGUUCAAGCCCAUCAUCAUCUGGAUUUUUGGGAAGUGGUCUUAACUGGUGUGCUGCCCUUCCCCUCUGCUCUCAACCCUAUUUUCAACAUAGCAGUCAGAAUAAUCUAAAAUAUAAACCAGAUCAUAUCACUCCUCUGCUCAACACCCCCUCCCAAUACCUUCAUGUCAUCCUCAGAGUUAUUGUCCAAGCCUCUAACUGUGGUCUACAAGUCUUUACAUGAUCUGUCCUGUUACAUUUUCCACUCUCGCUCCAGACCUGACCUAAGAGGCUUUUCUCUGAACUUGCUAAACAUGCUCUUACCUGAGGGUCCAUUCCCACUGCCUCUGCCUGGAAUGCUCUUCCCCAGACAUGCAUCUGCGUGGAUCAUUUCCAUGCCUCCUCAGGUCUUUGCCCUCAUGAAGCCUUCCCUGACAACCCUAUUUAAGAUUGUAAUCCCCUCCCACAGUGGCCCCUAUCUGCUAGAGACUGAAUGUUUUUGUCCCCCCAAAAUUCCUAUGUUGAAGCCUUAAUCUCAACAUAGGAGGUUUGGCCUUUGUGAGUUAGUUUUAGAUGAGGUCAUGUGGGUAAUAGAAUUAGUGCAUUUAUAAGGGCGUGAAGAGCCCUCACUGUGAGGAAACCAGAAUGUAAGCCUUCACCAGAACUUCUUCAUGCUGGCACCCUGGUCUUAGACUUCCCAGCCACUAGAUCUGUGAGAAAGAAAUGUUUGUUGUUUAAGCCACCCUGUCUAUGGUACUCUUGUUACAGCAACCUGAACUAAGACACUAUCCCUCUCCCCUGCUUUCUUUUUCUGUUAUCACCAUAAUUAAUGUUUUACUUAUAUAUGAUUUGUUAAUGUAUGUCUCUUCCCACUAGAAACCGAAUUCUAUGACAGCAAGGGUUUUUGUUUUCAUUAUUGUCAUAUUACCUGUGCCUGGCAUGUGAUAAGCCCUAAGUACUUGUUGACUGAAUUAACAUAUGAGAUCUGUGAGUCUGAAAAAAGAAGUACAUCAUUCCUUCACAUGUCAUUUUGAGCCACUGUUAACAGAUUACAUAACUGUUAUUGGAAGUGCCUCACUACUCCAUUUGGAAAGUAUUCCUGGAAUACACGAUGAAUGACUCAGUAGAAGUUCUGGCUAUGGGGGAGUGCCAUCAAUAAAUAAAAAUAAUACCAUUGUCUGUUGGUUAUAAGUUGCUGUCACAGACUAUGAAGGUAUUUGAAUUGUAUUUUCAGGAAGAGAAACAGAUAUGCAACCAAUCUGAUUUGGUUCCACACCCUGCCACAGAAGUCCCAAAGGAGAAGCAAAUGCCACUUGUAGACUCAAACUCUGGACUUCAUUCUCAGCACCAUCUCUUAACCUACUGAGUAAAUCCUAUGAACCUGACUAGGGUGGCAACUGAAGUUGUAGUACUUUCUGUCUUCAAAGGAGGGUGAACCUGGAGUAUGUUGGAAGAAGUGUUAGGUUCAUUAGAGACACCUCUUUCAUAACUGCUGUCACCUAGAAUGUCUAUUCUCUAAGCACCUUCUUGAAAGAAGCACAUUCCCCCAGGAGGAGGAAAUGGUUUGUUUUCUUUAGUGACAGUUGGCCCAGGAUCCUAAGGUAAAGGAGUAUGGGCACUAGACAAAAUGAGUUUUAUAAUAGUCGAUUGGAAGGAAUGGAAGUUUUUGAAUCACAGGCUUCUGCCUUGAAAGGGCAAGUCCGUGGUGGUCAUGAACCACCCAGAGUGUGUACAAGGCUCCUGCCAGAAGAAAUGCCUGUAGGAUUAAAAGCAAAACAGCAGAAUCAAAAAGGAAGGGCACGAUGAUGCCCAGGUGCAGCCUAUAUUAUUAACAGACAAGGAAAGAAUCCAAAUAAAAGUUCUGUAAACCA